AGGGCUCGGUCGCCAGCAACCGAGCGGGGCCCGGCCCGAGCGGGGCCUGGGGGUGCGACGCCGAGGGCGGGGGAGAGCGCGCCGCUGCUCCCGGACCGGGCCGCGCACGCCGCCUCAGGAACCAUCACUGUUGCUGGAGGCACCUGACAAAUCCUAGCGAAUUUUUGGAGCAUCUCCACCCAGGAACCUCGCCAUCCAGAAGUGUGCUUCCCGCACAGCUGCAGCCAUGGGGUCUGAGGACCACGGCGCCCAGAACCCCAGCUGUAAAAUCAUGACGUUUCGCCCAACCAUGGAAGAAUUUAAAGACUUCAACAAAUACGUGGCCUACAUAGAGUCGCAGGGAGCCCACCGGGCGGGCCUGGCCAAGAUCAUCCCCCCGAAGGAGUGGAAGCCGCGGCAGACGUAUGAUGACAUCGACGACGUGGUGAUCCCGGCGCCCAUCCAGCAGGUGGUGACGGGCCAGUCGGGCCUCUUCACGCAGUACAAUAUCCAGAAGAAGGCCAUGACAGUGGGCGAGUACCGCCGCCUGGCCAACAGCGAGAAGUACUGUACCCCGCGGCACCAGGACUUUGAUGACCUUGAACGCAAAUACUGGAAGAACCUCACCUUUGUCUCCCCGAUCUACGGGGCUGACAUCAGCGGCUCUUUGUAUGAUGACGACGUGGCCCAGUGGAACAUCGGGAGCCUCCGGACCAUCCUGGACAUGGUGGAGCGCGAGUGCGGCACCAUCAUCGAGGGCGUGAACACGCCCUACCUGUACUUCGGCAUGUGGAAGACCACCUUCGCCUGGCACACCGAGGACAUGGACCUGUACAGCAUCAACUACCUGCACUUUGGGGAGCCUAAGUCCUGGUACGCCAUCCCACCAGAGCACGGCAAGCGCCUGGAGCGGCUGGCCAUCGGCUUCUUCCCCGGGAGCUCGCAGGGCUGCGACGCCUUCCUGCGGCAUAAGAUGACCCUCAUCUCGCCCAUCAUCCUGAAGAAGUACGGGAUCCCCUUCAGCCGGAUCACGCAGGAGGCCGGGGAAUUCAUGAUCACAUUUCCCUACGGCUACCACGCCGGCUUCAAUCACGGGUUCAACUGCGCAGAAUCUACCAACUUCGCCACCCUGCGGUGGAUUGACUACGGCAAAGUGGCCACUCAGGGGCAGGGAGUCGGCGGCUUAGCUUCCUCUGGAGCACGGUUCCAUCAGCCAGAUGCGCUCACAUCCAGCUCUUAGCGGCUCCUGCAAAAACUCGCUCUGAUCAAAGGGAGGUGAGUGUAAAAAUGCGGCCCGGGCUUUGUCUCCAACUCCCCCCGUGAUUCCUGGACCACGCAGGCCAUAUCACUCGGACACCACGGAUACAAACCCUCACUCCCCUGGCCCCUAGAGCUGAGCAGAGCGCUGGGUUCGACUUCCAUCUAGAGCAGAGGUCGAUGGGGGGGAGGUUGCCCCUGCCCACAGCUCCACCCGUGAUAAGUAGGCAGGCUUUUCCAUAAUUAAUCAAAACCUAGGCCGUUCAUCUGUGGGCCAGGGCUGAGCAGAGACCACCGGAGUCCCUGAGGGGGCCCCUGAGGCUGCAGGGGACAGGCCAGGCCCCCCCCCUCCCCCCCCCCGCAAAAGAGCAGGUUGUGGUUAUAGGGGCAGGAUGACAGUGGGAGAUUUUGACAUCCUCAAGAGGCAGAGGAGCAGGACGCCCCUGCCAGCUUCAUCCGCACAUCCCUUGGGGCAGAUACAGAAGGAAGAAUGUGCAUUGUUGGAAACUGGGGAAUACGGUAAACAAAGAGAAGUGGGAGCUGACCUUACCAUCUCUGCCAUCCGCUCAGCCAUGAGAAGGAGCAAGGCCCAGCGUGGGUGAACCCUGAGGACACCCCGCUCAGUGAGAGAAGCCAGACCCAGAGGCUACACCGUGCGAGACCCCAUUUCUAUGAAAUGUCCGGGACAAGCCAGUGCUCAGAGGCAGGAAGGGAUGCUUGGGUGUGGGGGCUGGAGGGUGACAACGGAUGGGGACGGGUUUUCUUUGGAGGAUGAAAAUGCUCUACCUUUGAUGGCGAAGAUGGUCUCCCCACUCUGUGAAUACACAAGCUCCUGCGUCGCACACCUGGUGAAUUGUAGGGCACACGAAUCUCACUGAAACUGUCCAGAAACAUCCUUCCCCCAGAUCAGCUCUCAGCAAAUCAGGAACAGUAAUCCAGAAUAAAAACUGGGCAGCCUUUCUGGAAGGCCGUCUGCCAUGGGUUACACAUGUGUCUCCUGUGGCCUAGCGGUUCUGUCUCUGGAACACGUGCAUACCGGUUCCAUGUCUAGGGAUAUCUGUAGCCCCGUUUGUUGUAGUGGAAAGUUCUAUGACCAGGGGAUGGGUUGAACCAGUGGAAUGUUAUGCAGCUGUGAAAAUGGGUUUGCUCCAUGAGGUUUGCUCUGUAUCUUUGGGCAUGGAGAGAUGAGCGCGACAACUUUAAGGGAAAAAAUAGGCUGUGGACUGGGACUCUUGUGAUUCCCGUUUUUUGUGGGGAUGUGGUUCUUGAACUGGGAAAGGGAGAUUUGCCCAAGUAUUGGUUGAUAUUAGUUUGAUGUCAUGGAAUUUGGGAUACCUUAAAAAUAUGCACUAACUUCUCAAUAUGGUUCUGUCUUUUUUUGUACUAAAAAAAAAAAAACCCACAUACUCCUCUUUCCAUAGUCAGAGGGGUGUAGCUCUGGGGAGGGAAGAGUGGGGUCCGCCAUUCCUAGGUGCUUCUUGAGCAAGCACCCCACAGUUCCCAAGUGGAAAAGGUUUUUGUUGUUGUUGCUUCGUUGGUUUGUUUUCAGAAUGGGAGUUAAAAACCAAACAAAAGGCCAAGCGCAGUGACUCAUGCCUCUAAUCCCAGCAUUUAGGGAGGCCGAGGUAGGGUUGCAUGAUUCCAGAGGUUCAAGACCGGCCUGGGCAACAUAGUGAGACCCCAUUCUCCACAAAAAGGGGGAAACAAGACAAAAACACAAAAACUGUGAAGACCCCCAAAGCCUGGCCCCCUUCCUCCCUGCUGAGCAGGUGAGGCAGUGCUGGAAAGAGGACAGAGUGGAAGGUCCUGGAAGCCCAGCCCAGCAUUGCUGAGCGCCUGCCGUGUGCAGGGGAGGGGUCCUAGCCCCUGGGUCUGCCAGGGAGAGGUGAGAGUGCAGAGGACAGCAGGCUUGCCUCCCUAGCCACACACCUCGCUGCAUGCCCUGGCCUCGCCAGGCUGAGGCUUAGGGUGCAGUACCCGGUUCGUUUUGAGAAGUCUCUUUCUCAGCUAGAGCUGUCUCAGUGGUAACGUUCUCUCUCUCUCUCUCCUCAUCUCUCUCUCCCCCCAUAUCUCUCCCCCUCUCUCUCUCUCUCCCCCUCUCCCCCUCUGUCUCUCUCUCCCCCAUCUCUCUUCCCCCUCUCUCUCCGCCUCUUUCUCUCCCCCCCUCUCUUUCUCUCCCCCUCUCGCCCCCUCUCUCUCCCUCUCCCCCUCUUUCCCCGCUCCCCCUCUCUCUCUCCCCUUCUCUUUCCCCCUUGCUCUCUCCCCCUCUCCCCCCUCCCUCUCUUUCUCUCUCUCUCUCUGUCUCCCCGCUGCGCGCGUGCGCCCCCCUCCGGCCCCCCCUUCCCCCCACCGCCGACAGUACCACCCUCCAUCAAGUGCCGACUCUGGGCCUUGUCACCUUGGGAGGACCAGAGUAGUGCAGUGACUUUGCCAAGGUCACACAGCAGGAGGCUGGGCCCAGCACACCCUAGACCUUCCUCUGCUUCCCUUGCCCCACUUGGAGGCACAGGCCGAUGGGGCAUCUGGGAGCCCACACCCUCCCUGCCCACCAGGUGUCUCCUGGGCCAGUGGCUUCGUGUCCUGGGCACGUGUCCUGUGCACAGCCCGGUGGGGGCAGCUGGAGGGGUCUCCAAGGCGGCGGCUUCCUGUCUCAGAGCAGGAUCCCCCGGCAUGUGCUCCAGCAGGCAGGCUUUGUAGUGGGAUUACUAAUGGGGCAGAUCAAAAGGAUGUUCCUAUUUCACUCAAGGAAAUAAAAUGUGCACGCAGCCGCCUUUCUCACGCUGAACUCAAGUUAGUCCUACAAGCCUGCACGCCAUGUUAGAUUAGCUCAGCACGCGGCCGGGCUGGCCCCGAGGUGGGUGGUGCCUGGUGCUGGUAGAUAAGGGUCUCUCCUCCAGAGCCCAGGACUCAGCGGCAUCCCGAAACACCCUGCCACGGGGAGAGUUGACUGAGGAUUAAACAGAGCGCGAGAGAUGUGAAGCCUGGCUGGAAGGCUGGGGAGCCACUCACGCUCUCUUAACUGGUUCCCUGCCAGCUGUCUGUGGGUGAGGCCUGCUGUGUGCCAGCCUCCCCGGGGACAUCUCGGGCUCUCUGGAGGUGUCUGGCAGGGAGAGCUUCUGCUGAGCUUGGGAAGGGGACGAUGACUUGGAUUCCCCAGAGGCGCCAUUCCAGGAAACGGCCCACUCGGCACCACCCAUCUCCUCCCACCUCCCCGCAUCCAGGCUGGAUGGGGGCUCCGGCAGGAACCAGGCCUCUCCUAAAACCCCAGCCCUGGGGUGUACUGAACUUAAUUACUGUAAAAUUCAAACCAAAUUGUUUCUGCUGCCUGGGAGAACUGUGUGUUCCUUCUGUUUGGUAAUGAGGCUGCCUGCUCCAGGUGAUUAACCCGGAGCCCAGGGGGAGGGAGCCCAGGGGGAGGCGGCAGAAGGCAGGGGCUGGGGAAGGGUGGGAGGGAGGAGGGCCCACGGAGGUGCGGGAAACUCCAGCCACUCCUCUGACCCGCUGGAGCCCACGGCUGGCCUGUGCCCUGCCUUUGGCUUCCUGCCUCAGUGAGCCUCUGAUUUAUGGCGUUGUGGGGCUGGACGCAUCGUGUGUGCCGCAAACUGCUGUGUGAAAUAUGUCUCCCUUGCUCUUCCCAGAUCUUCCCUGUCACUCUGACCCUGGUGAGGCCUUUGGGGCCCCUUCCCAUGUGUGGGCUUAGGGGGUGUCACAGUCACGCAGAAGCGUGGGGAGAAUCUGCAGCUAAGACCAGGCGGAGCGGAUCCCGGGCCGGGCCAGAAUGAGUGGGUCCCAUGCUGGCUCUUGGCCUAGUGUUUAUGCUGCAUGUCUGGAGGGUGAUCUAGGAGAGGAGUGGUCUGGAAAGAAGGCCUCGUUUAGUCUCUCCCUCGGCACUGCGGACAUUGGGGCCGUAUCCUUCUCUGGGCUGGGGCCGUCCUGGGCACUGCACGGUGCUGAGCAGUGCCCCUGGCCUCCACCCACUCCAUGCCAGGCACACCCCAACCCAGCUGUUUCAACCACAACAUCGGCAGGCACAUCCACUCCCAUGGGGGCAGGGCCACCCAUUGAAGACACCUGGGUCUCCAGGCUCCCUGCGGGCCCUUCCUUCCUUUCUCCCACUGCUCUCGGCUUUCGGGAUCACGCCCUCUAAUACCCCCGGUUCUGCUGCCCAGGAGCUCCGGGGGGGACACAUCUCCCCAGAGGAGGGUCGGGGGCUUUUCUAGACCGAGGCUCGUGGUGUGGCUCGAGGGCCUUUGCCAGCUCGGCAGCCCCCAGUCUUCUCUACCAUCCUUCAUGGACAGAGCUGGUUCGGGGGCUGCAGCUGGUUGCUGCCUGGCAUCAGAGGAGCGGGUCUGCUUACGGGGUCAGGCAGAGGCAGGACCCCCUCGAGGGGCACUGGCGAGGGAGCCCAGGGGUCAGCCGUCAGAGAAGCAGGAGAGUCAGAGGAGGGGGCUCGCAGGGCCUGGCCCUGAGUCAGAAAUGGUGGAGUUCUCCCCUCUGCCAUCUCAGGGCAUCCCGGCUCAUGGCUGUUCCUCAGCCGUCGUGGAUGAGUCGUAACCUGGAGAGUGAGAGAGAACCUCCAGGGGCAACUGCUGGCAAGGAGGGAUCAGGGGAGGCCGGGCCCCUGUACCCCUGACCACAUGUCCUCUCCCCACCCAAGGUGUGACCCUUCAUGGGGCCUGUGGUUCAUACCUGGAGCUGUCUGCCUGGGUGCAGACCCUCCCCUCCUAGUGCUCUGCCUCAGUUUCCCUCCUAGGGCUGUUGGAAGUGACAUGGAACAGCACUUGGGUGGUGCCUGGCACAGAAGCAGGACUGCUGUGGCUGUUGAGGCCCCUUCAGGGCAGCAUGUGGAGGAGAAAGGCAGGUCCUGGUGGCCUGGGGUCAGGUGUGCAGCUGCCUGCUUGUCAUGUCCCUGCAGGGGCUCACAACACUGAUAGACUCGAGGCUACUUUCAUUUAGGGAGGGCCAAAGGGGACAUCGGAGCCUCCCCAGGCACCUGGUGGAUGUGUGGGCAGCAUGGAAGGCUGCGGAAGGCCAUGGAAGGCCCGUGACCUUGCCUGGCCUGGCUGGCCGGGAGGGGCAGGGAGCCGCUUUCUGUGCUGCCAGGAAUGGCCCCGCAGCCGAAGCCCAGGGAGCCCUGGGAGCCGGCGCCUAAUUGUUUUGUUGACGCGGCUGCCGAGCACUUCCAGUAGGUUUCCUAAUGAACUGGUUUGUUAUCGGCCUCACUGCAGCGCUGAUAAUUACAUCAGAAACAGGGGGCCCACUCGUCCUUCCCACGCGUUCUGUGAGCCAUCAGCGCAGAUGCGGGCGCCUCUGCCCCUUCCUCGGUGUUUAACGCUUUGUGUGCCAAGGCACCUGCCACCCACACCCACCCCAGACAGAUGGUCGAGAUGGCUGUGAGAGGAGUGUGACCGCCACUCGCCCCGGUUGGUGUCUGCUUGGCAGUGGUCACCGCGCAGGUCACUGUUCAGCUGCUGGGAAGGCAGUGGAUGAGGCCAUCGAGGUCCAGGGAGGAGACAGGACACGAACAAGGGUGGAAGGAGGAAUUUCUGCUCCUAGAGAGGGUGCAGGGACGCUGCAGCUGCGGCCUGGUGUGUCUGCCACCUGGGUAGCCCAGUCCACAGCCCAGGCAGCUGAAAGCACCAGACAUGUAUCCUCUCUCAGUUCUGGAGGCAGAGGCUGAGAUGGGUGUGUGGCGGGCCGAGCCCCCUCAGGGCGCCAGGGAGACCACCCUGCCUCUCCUGGCUUCAGGGCUGGCCGAGAUCUCAGGGCUGCUUGGCUUGCAGGGGUGUCGCCCUCUCCUCUGCCCCAUGGUCACGCGGCCCCUCCUCCCUGUCUUUGUGUCCUCUUGUCUGCUUCUAAGGGCACCAGGUGCUGACCCCCGGCAGGCCCUGAUCCCAUAUGUGAAUCAUGCACUGAUGACAGCUGCUACCACCCUGCUUCAGAAAAGCUCCUCUGUGAGGCCCCGGGUGCAGGAUGCUGAGUAGCGCGGGGAACAGCACUGCUGGGGAGGAACGAAAAUUGCGAGGUCCCUGAGCGGGGGACCUGGCAGAGGCCAAACGUCAGAGGUCGGGGGCUGCAGUAAGGGCCUUUGAAGUUAGAUUUCAUCACCAUGUGCGGGGGGGAGGCACUGGGCAUUUCAGCAAGGGAGAGGGGCCACUGGCUGGAGAAGGGACUAUGGGAGAGAUGGGGCAGGGAGCCCGGCGUGGAUGGCCGCCGUCUAGACGGGCAUGGGGUCUGUGGGCGUGGGAAGAAGGGGACAGCGUGUGCCUGUGUUUUAGGGGUGGUGCCUGUAGGACCUGGUGAUAGGACAGAGGUGGGGGCACAGGGGAGGGGUGGGGACUUGGGCAUGUAGGUGUGCGGUGGUGCUGGGAGCGCACAGAGGGACAUGGAGGAGCCAGGACUGGGUGUGCUGUUGAGAUGCGUCAGAGCCUGCCUUCCAGUGUGGGAGCCACGGGCCACACGUAGCACCGUAUCCAUUAACCAAAAUGAAAUAGGAUGAACCCUCCACUCCUCAGUCAGGCCAGCCGCGGGUCAAGCCCUUUGCUAAUAGCCGGGUGGGCUGGUGGCCGUGUCCUGGGCAGCGCAGGUGCAGGUCAUCGCCGUCACCACAGACAGUCCUGUCACCGUGCAGCUGAUGCGUCCUGUGGAGGGGUCUGCAGCUCGGGGGCGGCGCCGGGGGCGGGGCAGGGGCAGUGUGAGGGAUGGGACGUGUUGAGCCAUAGAUGUCCUGUCGGCAGCUAUGAGAUGCUGUGCCCUCCCCACGCCAGGAUCGCUGUUUCUAAGGCCCCUGCCCGUCCCCAUCCCUGUCCACAGCAGGGCAAGCACCAGCCAUGCAAUGUCUGUCACCGUCGGCUGUAGAACCGCCCGCUGGUGGCUGGCAUUGUCCUCAAUGUUCCGCCCUGGUUCCUGGAUCAGGGGGCUGGGAGUUGGCGCUGCAGCUGACGAGAGCAUUCAUGAUCCCCGUGGUCAGAUGCUAUUUGGGUUGAUGAUUUUAUCGGACCACAUAUAAUCAUUUUCUCAUUAGGCCGGUGGCUGUGUCUUCUCUCUGCCACUCUACUGUUUUACAUGAGCAGACUCUAGUAUCUGUUCAGGCUUUUAAAAAAGAGAUGGCCUCUGGUGAAAGCUCAGUGCUGUUUAAAUCAGGAAAGGUGGCAGAUGAGCCCCCUGGGCUCCAAGGCAGCAGUGGUAGCCCACUGUGUCUGCAGGUGGCCAGGGUCCUGUGAUGAUGCUGCCAGCCAGGCUGCUGCACACUGAGAGCUGGGGGCCCACGAGCCUCGGUGCUGGACGCCCCCACAGUGUGGAUCAGAUCGCAAGGGGCUGGCCAGGGCAGGGCAGAGCCUGCUAGGAGGAGGGAGAGGGCUGGGAGCAGCCAGGGUGGACCCCUCAACCUGGAUCAGAUCACAAGGGGCUGGCCAGGGCAGGGCAGAGCCUGCUAGGAGGAGGGAGAGGGCCCGGAGCAGCCAGGUCGGACUCCUCAACCUGGGGACCCUCCCCCAGCAGCUGCAGGCUUGAGUGUGUGCAGCACUUAUGUGCGAGCAUGUCGUUUGUGUGUGUGUUUCCCUGGGAAUCAGACCCUGGCAGGGGCCCCCAGUCUAUAGAGUGGGUGCUAUGGACCCCAGCCGCUGUGAGGCAGAGUGUGCGCCCCACCAAGGGGCAGGCUGCCGAAAAGUCAGCUUCACAGGGAGCUUGUUUUAGGAGGAGGUCCUUGUGUUAUGGAAAUGUAGGCCACAGACUGAGGCGCACACAGGGCCGGUGUACAGUGUGGGGAAUCUUUUUUUUUUUUUUUUUGAGGUGGAGUUUUGCACUGUCACCCAGGCUGGAGUGCAGUGGUGUGAUCUCGGCUCACUGCAACCUCUGCCUCCCGGGCUCAAGCGAGUCUCCUGCCUCAGCCUCCCUGAGUAGCUGGGACUACAGGUGCGCCACCACACCUGGCUAAUUUUUGUAUUUUUAGUAGAGGUGGGGUUUCUCCAUGUUGGCCAGGCUGGUCUGGAACUCCUGACCUCAAGUGAUCCACCCGCCUUGGCCUCCCAGAGUACUGGGAUUACAAGCGUGAGCCACCGCGCCUGGCCAUGGCGUGGGGAAUAUUCACAACCCUACCCCAUCCGGACUCCUGGCAGCAUGGAGUGGUGUCACCUUGGAUGGGGAGCACGGUCCCAGGUCUCCACGGGCUUGGGCAACCCCUGGGGUUCCUGCUGACCUCAGUGCCCCUGCCCAGACCCCAGUUUCUCACUUCCGUGCGAUGUGGCAUUUCUACACUGGAGUCGCUGGUGACAUCAGUGGCGCCUGUUGCCGCGGUGCCCCCGGCGGUGUCGGUGGUGCGUGUUGCCAUGGCGCCUGCCUGGUGGAGGAAGUGUCCCGCGGUGCCCCCGGCGGUGUCGGUGGCGCGUGUUGCCAUGGCGCCUGCCUGGUGGAGGAAGUGUCCCGCGGUGCCCCCGGCGGUGUCGGUGGCGCGUGUUGCCGUGGCGCCUGCCUGGUGGAGGAGGUGUCCCGCGGUGCCCCCGGCGGUGUCGGUGGUGCGUGUUGCCGUGGCGCCUGCCUGGUGGAGGAAGUGUCCCUCCGUUUCUGGAUUUGCCUUAAUAGCUCAGAGAAGGCUGAGGGAAACCUGUGAGUGAUUGUAAACAUCCCAUGCUAGGGAAGGGCUUGUGAGGCCACACAGGGUGGCUUCCACCAGAAUCGACACUUUAAAGAGCACGGGCUGGCAGCAUGUGUGGUGUGGAGUCAGCAGGGCGGGGAGAAAAGAACAAGGCACGUGCCCCAUGGCCAUCGGGUGAUGGGGAUGGUGCCUGUUCACGAAGAAGAGUCACCAAGGGAAGGAGGUGAAUGGUAACCAAAGCCACCAAGAUGUCAAUCUCACCGUACACAGGAUUCUUAAAUAUGUAGUAAAAGGCUGUAAAGCCCCACGUGGCGCAUCAGUCGGCCAUCCAGGCUUCGUGGUUUUGUUUUUUGUUUUGUUUCUUGAGACAGUCUCCAAAAACUCCAGAUUGGAGUGCAGUGGUGCGAUCAUAGCUCACUGCAGCCUUGACCUCCUGAGAUCAAGCAAUCCUCCUACCUCAGCCUCCCGGGUAGCUGGGACUACAGGUAUUGCACCACCAUGCCCAGCUAAUUUUUUGUAGUUUUUGUAGAGUUGGGGUCUCACUAUGUUGUCCAGGCUGGCCUUGAACUCCUGAGCUCAAGGGAUCCUCCUGCCUUGGCCUCCCAAAGCACUGAGAUGACAGGCGUGAGCCGCCGCGCCUGGCCUGUGCAGGCCUUGGUGGAGCUGCUCCUUCGGUCCUGAUGGGGAGCAUUUCCCAAAUGUGCCCCAUGGAAAAGGCAAGGCGCAGAGCAGGGACCGUAGGAUGUCAUUGACAUGAAAAGCAGAGGACCGCUGCCCUGUGUGUCGGGAGGCUGGGGCCUCAGGGCAGAGAGCGCGUUGGCCACCUUCCCUUUUGUUCUUCUGGAGCUGGGUACUGGGUGCAGUGUUGGCUGUUCCAGAAAGUCUAUGAGUUCUGUCUCCGUUUUGGCUUGGAGUUCUCCUGUGGGAGGUGCCCAGCAAGGAUGAUUCCCCUCGGCCACCAGUGAGAUGGGAACCCUCCUCCUCCUCAGCUCAGCAGAGCCGUCGUGGACCUGGGGCCCCCAGCUUCUUUGGAUCUCAGGCAUGGGGGGCGCAAAUGUCAGUCGGGAGCUGUCAAGCUCUGUGGAAGGUUUCUGCAUGUUUGCCCGAGCCCCACCAGGAGGGGCUUCAAAAGUGCUUGUCCAAGUGCAGAGCAAGGCAGGGCACAGAGGCAGAGGCAGACACAGCCCCCAGCUGGGCCAGGGCUGGUGGCCAAGGGGCUUCCUCAGUGUGUAGCCUCCGUGGCAGCCUCCAUGUGUAGUACAUGGUCAGUAGAAGCCCCAUUAACAGCAGGGGGGACUCGGCCUCUGGGGAGCGGAUUUCUUUUGCAAUAUGAUGUUAAAGGAAGGUCUGGCAUUCAGUAUGUUUUUUAUUUUAUUUUUUAUUACAGUUUACAAAAGCACUCCAGUUUCAUUGGAUUUCAGGCAUUUUGCAUGGGAUCGUUAUGGCUCAGAAGGCGUAAUCUCAGGCAUUAGAUUAGAGUGACAGGCUUGGGAAUUCAGACCGGAGAACAGCUGCCCUGCCUGUUCCCUUGUAGGUGACUGGCAGGUCUUGCUUUAUAACAGGAAGUGCUCCCAUGGUGGCCCUGACUUGCCCAGCCUGUGGGGUUUGCUUGUGUUACCUCAUUUAAAACCCCUGGCAGCACGAGGUUGGUCCAUCUAGUUCCCUAGAAAGGUGCCAUGGACUGAAGGUCUGUGUCCCCUCAGAGUCAUCUGUUGAGUGCUCAUACCCCUCCCUAGGGUGAUGGUAUUAAGAGAUGGGGCCUCUGGGAGGCGACGAGGGCAUGAGGGUGAUGCCCUCAUUGAUGGGAUCAGUGCCCUUAUGAAAGAGCCCCCAGAGAGCUCCCUCGCCCCCUCCAUCAUGGGAGGACUCAGUGAGAAGAUGCCAAGAAUCAGGAAGUCACCCUCACCAGACACCAGACCUGCCAGUGCCCUGAUCUUGGACUUCCCAGCCUCCAGAACCAUAAGAAAUAAGCAAUUUGCUUAUGAGCCCCCAGCUUAUGGUAUUUUGUUUCAAUAAUGGACUAAGACAAAAGGUUCAUUCCAGUCACUUCCUCACAUGCCAUUUCCCUCAUCCCUGCCUCCAAGGAAUGUGCAGGGUGGAUUUCUGAGCCUUUAGUUGCUGCUUUCUUUCCUUUUGGCAGAGAUACUUUCAGGGGAACCUGGUCACAUAGAACAACCUCCGGUUCCAGUAGUGCUGGGCACACACUGGGUAGCAGUGGGCAGUGGAGAGGAUUGCAGGGCACCAGAAGGCCCAUUUGUUUCCUUUCUCUUUAAACAUGAUGAGCAGGUCUGUGCAAAUACCCCAAAGUCCAAGGAUGCUGAGAGGCCAAAGAAAGAAGCUGGCAUUCAGUUUCUCAGAGAGAAACAUUUAAUAAGGAUUUACAACGAGAAGCCAUGUCUGUGUCUUGGGUGGCGGUAGUGAGACAAGACGGUGGAUCCCUGCACCAUCACCCCCAGACCCAGGGCUUAUAUACCAUAGGGAAGGGUUGUUUUGGGAUGUGCAAGACAAUUGAAAUAUGGAAACCUCAAGGGCCAUUUGACCAAAGGGCAAGAUUUACAGUAAGUACCUGCUCUUAUACAAGGAGCAGUAGAUGAACUGGAAAUCUCAGAGGCCUUCCCAGAAUGGGGGUUAAUCAAAAGCCAACAUGGCAGGUUAGCAUCCAAGAUGGAGUUGCUUUGGCCUCCACACCUGCUGUGACCUCAUUUCUGAGAGACAUAUGCUCCAGGGGCUUCUUGAGAAAGGAACACAGGCAGUAAAGUUUUGAGACUUUUCUCAUUUGAAAACAGGGCCUGAGGGUGGCACCCUCAUGGAGGAGAUCAGAGCCCUUAUAAAAGAGCCCCCAGAGAGCUCCCUCACCCCUUCUACCAGAGGAGGACACAGUGAGAAGGCACCAUCUAAGAACCAGGAAGUGACCCUCACCAGACACCAAAUCUGCCAGUGCUUUGAUCUUGGACUUUCCAGCCUCCAGAACCUUGAGAAAUAAGGAAAGGGCAGAAUUUGAAAAUGAAACCAAAAACUCCACAGGAUGGUUAGGCAACAAAGUAGAAGAACUUGUGCAGGAGAAGCUGCUGUCUGGGUGGCGGAUAGUUUGGCUGGGUAUCGAAGUCCCUUCGAAGGCUGCACCCAUCCGUGGUUCUCAUUCAGUGCUGCUGGCACAAAGAUGCUCCUCUGAUUCCUCAUCCUUGGUGUGGGACCUGUUUUUCUCCCUUCUGGAGGCUUAUUGAACCCUUUUUGUGUCCCAAGUGUCCUGAAGUCCCCUCAUUGGGUACCUGAUACGUGUCUGAUUUUUGUCACUUGCCCCUCCUUGGGCCUUUCCAUCCAUCUUUUCCAACCUUUCCCAUGAUUCUGGUAAACUUUCUUGAAUGGUUUCAUUGAUUAUUUGCUCUCCUGUCUUUCUUGUUUCUAUUUCAAACUCCCAUCACUCGCUAUUGGGCUUUCAGAACUAGUGUUCCACUUUAUCUUCCCCACCUCCGUUUUCUACGUUGUCUUUUUUGUUUUUGUUGUUGUUGUUGUUGUUGUUGUCUUCAAGACAGGAUCUCACUCUGAAAUGAGACAGAGUCUCAGCCUAGAGUGCAGUGGUGCAGUCAUAGCUCACUGCAGCCUCAAACUCCUAGGCUCAAGUGAUCCUCCUGCCUCAGCCUCCUGUGUAGCUCGGACUACAGGUGUGUGCCACCACACUGGCUAAUUUUUUGUAGAGAUGGGGUCUCGCCAUGUUGCCCAGGCUAGUCUUGAACUGACCUCAAGUGAUCCUCUCGCCUCGGCCUCUCAAAGUGCUGGGAUUAAGGCGUGAGCCACCACACUUGGCCUCUUUGUCUUUUUUAUUAAUUUGUUUUCUGGAAGAGUUCCUCAGCUUCCUCACUUAACCUGUCUAUUGAUGUGUUUUUAUUGGUGUUUUUCAUUUCUGCCCUUUUUUGUCUUCUGAAUAUUCCUUUUGUUAUAAGCCCCGUUCUUCUUUCAUGAUGUAGUAUCUUUUAUUUCUGAGGAUAUUGAUUGACGAUAGGUUUAAAUUCUUUUUGAAAAUGUCUUCUCUGGCUGGACACGGUGGCUCACACCUGUGAUUCCAGCACUUUGGGAGGCUGAGGCGGGCGGAUCACCUGAGGUCAGGAGUUCAAGACCAGCCUGGCCAACAUGGUGAAACCCUGUCACUACUAAAAAUACAAAAAAUUAGCUGGGCAUGGCGGUGGGUGCCUGUAAUCCCAGCUACUGGGGAGGCUGAGGUAGGAGAAUCACUUGAACCCAGGAGGCAGAAGUUGCAGUGAACCGAGGUUGUGCCAUUGCGCUCCAACCUGGGCAACAAGAGCAAGACUCCGUCUCAAAAAAAAAAAAAAAAAAAUCUUCUCUGUCCUCUGUUUCUUACCAGGUUUUUGUUUUUUUUUUGAUAGUUUAUUUUGAUCUCUGGGGAUCAUAGUGCAGGCCCAUCUCUCUGAUGCUUGGGGGUAACGAUCUAGUGUAAUGAUUACAAGUGAGGGACUAGGUGCAGUGGCUCAUGCCUGUAGUGCAGCACUUUGGGAGGCUGAGGCAGGAGGAUUGCUUGAGCCCAGGACUUCGGGGUCGGCAGUGAGCUGCUGUGAUCACGCCACCACAUUCCAGCUCCAGCCUGAGCAAUAGAGUAAGACUGUCUGAAAAAAAAAAACAAAACCCCAAAACCCAAAAAACCCAAGUGGGCAAUGGAUGCUGGUGAUGGGUUGGGAUGCAAGGGGAUAGCGGGGAGGGCCUCACUCGGUGCUUUACCCGGGGAGGUCUGGGUGGGCUGUGGAUGCAGGGGAAGGGCGGGGAGGGCCUCACUUGUUGCUUUUCCUGGGGAGAUCCGGGUGGGCUGUGGAUGCAGGGGAAGGGCGGGGAGGGCCUCACUCGGUGCUUUUCCCGGGGAUACCUGGGUGGGCUGUUAUGGGGGAGCCCACAUCAGGCCCUUUGGGUCUCUCCCCUUGGGCCAGCCGGAUUGCACAGGGAGUAGCCCUCCAGCCUCCUGCCUGGGCUCCUAAGGGUGUCACCCACAUCCUCCACUGUGCCCAGUGUCCCCAGCCCAGACACCCACCUUCUCUGGCCUCCCCAGUAAAUGAUCCUAGGGAGUCCAGCGAGGAGGGGCAGGCGGCCGCCAGGGUGCCAGGAGGGGUCGGGUGCUGCGGCAGUCCUCGCGCAGACCUCCGUUUUGAGCACCCCCACCCUUGUUUCCAGGGGACCCUGGGCCAUGAGGCGUGGGGUGCGUGCCCGCCACCACCAUCCGUGUCUCUGCUGGGAAUGGCUCCCUGGUGGCCGUCCGUCUGCUCGCCACGUCCCACCCCCAGCCUGCUGUCGUCUCCUUUUCCAUCCUCCCUGUCCUUGCAGGUGUGUCCUCCCUAAAGGCACUUUCUCGUGGCUUCAGGAGAGAGAUGGGUGGCGUGGGCUUGCCAGCCUACCAAGGCAUCACUUAGAGCCAGGAGCCAUGAGCGUGGCCUCCUUCCUGCAGUUGCCUCUGGCUGCCCAGGAGGGAUGUGGUGUUGCCUGGCAGGGAGUGGAGACAGUGAGGCCUUCUAGGGGUCCUCCCUUGAAGGGUCAGCAGACCAAUGUGGAAGUCACCAAGGAUGAAGGCCAGAGCCUGGGGGAGGGUGGAGCUGGACACCCCUGGGAAGUCUGGGAGAGGGGCUGAGCCUCCACAGGCCAGGGGAGCAGGGGAGGAAUGGGGCCGGGGCCGGGGUGGCAUCUGGGGCCACUCCCGGUCUCUUGCUGUUGGCGUUGGGAGGGAUCUCGCACCACAGCAGGGAAUCGAGGCCCCGGCUCCCCUCAGGCUCUCCCUUCACCGGCAAUGGGCGGCGGGCGACGGGUGACGGGUGACGGGUGAUGGGUGCAGCACCCGCCCCGCCCAUAGGAGAGCCCUGGUCCACUGUGGCCUGUGGAUGCCGCCCCUGACGUCAGCAUCUCUCUCUGGCCUCCCUGGGAGCAGUCUCAGAGCAGUGAAGAGCUCUUCACGUCCGGUGCUGUGGCGAUACUAAGUAAUAAGAUCUCCAGGUUUUAUUGGGCAUUAAUAUUUAUUCCCAUGAAAAGGUUAAAUUUAUUUCACUUUAAAGCCCUGGAGAGUGCAAGGUGGAGCCAUAGUCGCCUCUCCUGGCAACGGCCCUGCCCACCACGUACCCACCUCUCCCACACAGGCCAGUCCUGGUGAUGGCCUGCAGGACAGGGCAGAUGUGUGGGGCAGUUGGGGGCACCCCCUUUUGGAAGGCACUGCUGCCAGUGGGGCCGGUGAGUGUGCAGAGCCCAGGGCCAAUGUGUGCCUCCUGCAGGCACCGGGCAGCCCUGGCCACUCCUCAGCUCUCUGACCCCUUCCCCCGCUCUCUGCAGCAGGCACCACACGAGCCAAUUUCGCUUGGCACGACGUCCUGAAGCAGGCCCUGGGCUCUGCGGCUGCUGGCUCUGAGCCCAUCGACAUUCUGAUUUGUAUUUUUUCAUGCUUUGGAAAAAAGAAAUCUAUUUAUCUCUGCGUCGGGUCCCGCUCUGCAUAACCGGAGGCAAACCAGCAGCCCCGCCCGCUUUCUCAUUUUCCUGGGAAGGUAGCAGCGGGUCCUCUGAGGCCUGCGUCAAGAAUAUCGGGCUGUCGGACGCGUCAGUCUUCAGGGGCAGGUGACGGCCGCACUGCUUCCAGCUCUUUGGCUUGGUGUUUGGGCACCAGCUGACGGGCCAGCCAGCAGCAGCGGUGCUGAGGUUAGUCCAGGUCCCCUGAACUCGACGGCCAUCAAUCCCGGGCCUGUCAUUUGCAAGCAGCUGCAGCAGCUGGUCGAGCCUCCUGCUAGACCCUCUCUCCACCCCAGGUUUUUCUUAAGGGUCUGUGACGGUAUCUGUCAGUGGAGACUCAUGUUAGCCAUGUCAGGAGGGCCUGUGUUGGAGAAGGAUGGAGGGAACAGCCCCGAGCCCAGGGGGCCUGGCUUUUGCUCUGUGAGGCUCGCUCCACACCCUGUUCACUUCCUGAUCCCCUUCCCCACCCUGCCUUGGUCCUUAAGGAGGUGAAGAUGGGGCACGGGGGUGCACGGCCACCUCCUGUAGAACCAGGGCAGGCCAGCCACCUUCUGAGUAGCUUCCGAGCUCCUGAGGCUUGGCCACCCGCACAUCAUGGGGUGGGUGAGGAGCAGAAGGAGGGGCCCUCCCCACGGCUGCCUGCAGUCUGGCCCUCCCCUUUUUAUCUGGGAAAAAGUGUCCUGUGGCUGCUGGGUGGGUGGCAGGGAGGCUGGCCGAAUCCCUGGCCAAUGAGUCCCGCUGGCAGGACCCCGAGAAGCAGAGGAGCUCGCUCCAGCUGGUGCCCCUCCACCCCGGCAGCAGCAGGACGAGCAGGCGUGCCAGCACAGCUCCUGGGCACCUGCCCCUUUCUGCUCCCGGGUCCCCUGGCUUCUCAUAUGUGCUUAUUUUGUCUCCCAGUUACACUGUGAGCUGCUUCAGGGCAGGGCCCAGCGUUGCACGGUAAAACUACAUUAAUUCAGACUCAUUAAUUCAGAGCCUAUAAUAGUUCAGACAUGGGAGACGUGACUCUUUUUGAGCUAAAAGUUGGAAACCGUUUUGCUCUGGGUUUUUAUGGCCACAAUUGCAGAACCUAAUCUAAGAUCAGUACCUUUUUUUUUUUUUUCCAGCAACUAAAAUCUUGGGAAAUUAAAGGUCCUUAAAACAUGCUUUCAAUUGUGAGCCAGACAGUUCUGAACCCGGCAAAGAGCAGGCACAGGGAUGCUCUGUCUUGGAAGGGGGUUUUGUCUGGGAACGCCACUUCCAGGAUUCAGACCUCAUGUGUGUCCCUCGGGAGCUUCCAAAAUAGGACUGCUUUUAGGUGGAGCGUAUUGGAACUGAUGUCAGUGAGAAAAUGGACACCCUCACACCCCCCAAAAAUUAGAAACAGAAGACCUCACUCCUCAGGCCGUGCCUCUUCUCUUCCCCAGACCCUGGGCAGGUCUCAGCAAACCCGGGAGAACCAGAGCCUGACUCCAGGUCCCAAAGUUGUCAUUUCAGGGACCUGAAUUGCUGUUUUCUCCCAUGUAUGAGUGUCUGGGCUCAUUAAGAUAACUGGGGCCAUCCCAGCCGGAAUGUGCAAAGUCCAUGGGCUCCGGGAGUUUGGAGCUGGGUCAGGUGGUGAGGCCGGGAGAGUCGCACCCCCUGGGCUCCGUCCGGGCAGCAGGAUCCAGGUCCCCAUGAGGCUGAGGUGCAAAUGGCCCCGCUCCCUGAGCUGCCCCUGAGUUCUGGGGGCAGCGUGCCCACAGUACAUGGCUGGCUUGGGCUGAUGGUGCAGAGGGCACAGGACCCAGAGCGGGGCAGAGCAGGAGGCCAGGACUCUCCAUGCCUGGAGCCGGACUGCUUCCCGGCAGGGGCAGUCAGAGGCCCGGAAGCCGGUAGUGGGGCGCGCGCAGCUGCCACGCUCAGUACAAACUGGGACUGCUGCCCAUGUCUGCAACAGACACACCUGCGAUUGCUCCCAGAGUGUGCUGAAGCUGGUCUGUGGGACGUGGUGUUCACCCCGAUGCUGUUACACUGCGAGUUACACUAGAAAAGUUACUUCAUGACUUAAGUCAGGCUUCAGCAAGCUUUUUCUUUUGAGACAGGGUCUCAGUCUGUCGCCCGGGCUGGAGUGCUGUGGCAUGAUCACAGCUCACUGCAGCCUUGACCGCCUGGGCUCAGGUGAUCCUCCCACCUCAGCCUCCCAAGUAGCUAAGACAGUAGGCGUGCACCACCACACUCACCUAAUUUUAAAAAUAAAUUUUUGUGGAGACAGCGUCUUGCUAUAUUGCCCAGGGUGGUUUUGAACUCCUGGCCUCAAGCGAUCCUCCUGCCUCAGCCUCCCAAAGUGCUGGGAUUACAGGUGUGAGCCACCAUUUGAGCCAGCCCAAACUUAUUGUAAAGGACCUGAUAGUGACUGUUUGCAGCUUUACAGGCCGUGCAUUCCCCAUCUUGAAUGUUCAGCCCUGCCCUUGUAGCGUGAACACAGCUGUGGAUGAUACAUAAAUGAAUGGGCCUGGCUAUGUGCCAAUAAAACUUUAUUCACAAAAACAAGUGGCAGGCCAGAUGUGGCCCAUGGGCCCACCUUAGAGGAUAUGCCUUCUCAAUAAAGAGAUUUAGAGAAAUAA